AGUAACCGCUGGGUGGACCUGGCCAGCGCUCCGAACCUUGUCCUCGCUGCGCGCCGGCCCCUCGGAGCCCCACAGCCCGGGAAGGAGGCCGCCGCGGGCCGGGCGCCCGCUCUGCCAAGCGGACCCGCAACCCGGAAAGGCGGCGCGGCGGAGCCUGGAGCCGGAUCCUGCUCAGACCGGGCCCCGGCCGGCCAGAGCCGCGGGCAUGUCGGAGGCGCGGAAGGGGCCGGACGAGGCGGAGGAGAGCCAGUACGACUCUGGCAUUGAGUCUCUGCGCUCUCUGCGCUCCCUACCCGAGUCCACCUCGGCUCCAGCCUCCGGGCCCUCGGACGGCAGCCCCCAGCCCUGCACCCAUCCUCCGGGACCCGUCAAGGAACCACAGGAGAAGGAAGACGCGGAUGGGGAGCGGGCUGAUUCCACCUAUGGCUCCUCCUCGCUCACCUACACCCUGUCCUUGCUGGGGGGCCCCGAGGCUGAGGACCCGGCCCCACGCCUGCCACUCCCCCACGUGGGGGCGCUGAGCCCUCAGCAGCUGGAAGCACUCACUUACAUCUCCGAGGACGGAGACACGCUGGUCCACCUGGCAGUGAUUCAUGAGGCCCCAGCGGUGCUGCUCUGUUGCCUGGCUUUGCUGCCCCAGGAGGUCCUGGACAUUCAAAAUAACCUUUACCAGACAGCACUCCAUCUGGCUGUACAUCUGGACCAACCGGGCGCAGUUCGGGCACUGGUGCUGAAGGGGGCCAGCCGGGCACUACAGGACCGGCAUGGUGACACAGCCCUUCAUGUGGCCUGCCAGCGCCAGCACUUGGCCUGUGCCCGCUGCCUGCUGGAAGGGCGGCCAGAGCCAGGCAGAGGAACAUCUCACUCUCUGGACCUCCAGCUGCAAAACUGGCAAGGUCUGGCUUGUCUCCACAUUGCCACCCUUCAGAAGAACCAACCACUCAUGGAAUUGCUGCUUCGGAAUGGAGCUGACAUUGAUGUGCAGGAGGGCACCAGUGGUAAGACAGCGCUGCACCUGGCUGUGGAAACCCAAGAGCGGGGCCUGGUACAGUUCCUGCUCCAGGCUGGUGCCCAGGUAGAUGCCCGCAUGCUGAACGGGUGCACACCCCUGCACCUGGCAGCUGGCCGGGGUCUCAUGGGCAUCUCAUCCACUCUGUGCAAGGCGGGUGCUGACUCCCUGCUGCGGAAUGUGGAGGAUGAGACGCCCCAGGACCUGACUGAGGAAUCCCUUGUCCUUUUGCCCUUUGAUGACCUGAAGAUCUCAGGGAAACUGCUGCUGUGUACCGACUGAAGCCAGGCAGGGUCUGGGAUCCUCAGGGCUCCACCUCUCCAUCUGGAAGCCGGAGCCAUAACUGCUGCAGUUUGGGCCCAGGCUAUGUGCUCUUCUGGUGCCCUAGGGACUGCUGUGGCCAGAGCCUGGGGCCAGCCAGUACAGUCCUGAGCCGAGGAGGAGGGACUGCAAGUGGAAGAGAGCCAGUCUGGAAGGAAGAGCUUUCCAGGUGGACAGGGCUUCUUGGAAGACCCCCAAAGCCCCAGGUAUCCUGGGUGAAGCCUGUUUGCCUCUCUUGAAAAUGGCAGGUGCUCUUGUUUUACCCAUGUUGGGUCAGCCUGAAACUGCCAACCAGUAGGAAGCAUGGACUCUCCUGAGUGAGAAGAGACUGAAAUAGGAGCAAGCAGAACCCUGAGAGGUGUCCCAUCUUAUUGCUGUUGAGGACCCUGAAACACCGUUGUUUAAAGACUUCACACAGAAGGCUCUGAACUGAGCCACUGGGGAAGGGAAGUUUCAGUAACAUGACACUAAAAUGGCAGAGACGUUAAAAAAAGUUUUUCCCUUCUAGAGCUGUUUUGCGCGCAUGCAUGUCUGUGUGCAUUGGGGCUUUUUAGACAGGCCUGCCCUGUGACUUUGUGGUAGAGGCAGAGAGAAGGAAAUUGUCCCCUGAGCACGGUAGGGCCUUGCUGGGUGGGGUCAGAGGCCAGUAGUUCCAGGCCUUUCUCUGUGUCCAGCACAGACCCUUGUCCUUGCUGUGGAAAUGAUGAGGGAUGGAGGGACAAGAGGAAGAAUGAGAGGACACACGCCCUGGAGCCCUCACCACUGCCCUGGGGGUUGCCAUCUGGAGGAGCCUGGGGAUAAGGGUAACCCAGGGAGGCUGGGCACGAGGGAGCUGACUCCACGUUUUUCCCCCCGUUCCUCACCUUCGAGGGCCCUGCUAGGUCACCCCUAUGCUGGCAUGAAGAGCAUGGGGCAAUAAACCAGCACAGUCUCUGACCACUUGGAGCGUCUCAUCCAGUGAGAGAGACAGCCGUUAAAAGCAUAAACAUCCAAAUAAAGAUGCCUUUCCAAGUU